GAUAAGCUACAACAUAAACACAUCUAGGUUCUUGUUCUUAGAAUACAGCAUGAAGAAUUUGCUUUCUUCUUUCUUCCUAACAUUUUCAUGUGAGAUCCAGAAAGGACACAUUGUCUCUGGCCAUUCGAAGAAAGAAAGAAAGAAAAAAAAAAAAGGUAUUUAGAGACAGAGAGAGAAAAAGGCUGAAAUGGGUUCGCUGGGUUCUAAAAAUCCGCAAACCAAACAAGCCCAAGUUCUUCUUUUGGGACUUGACUCAGCUGGGAAGUCUACUCUCCUUUAUAAAUUAAAGCUUGCUAAGGAUAUUACCACCAUCCCUACAAUAGGUUUCAAUGUGGAAAUGAUCGAGUUGGAAAGGAAUCUUUCACUCACAGUCUGGGAUGUUGGAGGACAGGAAAAAAUGAGAACUGUUUGGGGCUGUUACUGUGAGAACACCGAUGGGCUGGUGUAUGUUGUGGACAGUACAGACAAACAGCGACUGGAAGAGUCUCAGAGACAGUUUGAGCACAUUUUGAAGAAUGAACACAUUAAAAAUGUGCCUGUUGUUCUAUUAGCCAACAAACAAGACAUGCCUGGAGCUCUGACUGCUGAGGACAUCACCAGAAUGUUCAAAGUGAAGAAGCUUUGCAGUGACCGGAACUGGUAUGUGCAACCCUGCUGUGCCCUCACAGGGGAGGGGCUGGCCCAGGGGUUCAGGAAAUUAACUGGAUUUGUGAAGAGCCACAUGAAAUCAAGAGGAGACACUUUGGCGUUCUUCAAGCAGAACUGAGGCUGCGAAAAAUCCAAGUCUCUACAGAGACACUGAUGAAGUUGAAAGGGUAAUUGUUUUUCCAUGCCAAAUGAGGAAAUCAAAUUAAUGAGUUGACAAACUUUUCCUGAGAUGUUAUUUCAUCUACAUUUAGUUAAACAACUUAGAAUGAUAUCUAGAAAAUAUUUAUUUUCAGCCAGGAACUUUAGCAAACUGUGGCAAUGAUCACUGGGAAUGAAAACGUAUAAUGUUCUACAAUUUUUGUUAUCACAUUGGAUGACUUUGAAUAUAGUAGUGACACUUGGGACCAAAUAAAUUAUUUUAUAUGACUACUAGAACAAAGUUUUAGUAAGCUGUCUGCUAAUAGAGUCAGAAUUCUUCCAGAUUGUUUCCAGCUGUAACAGGUAUUGAAUUUCCACCGUGCUCCUAUGUAACAGCUGGGUGGUGUAAAAAAUGAACUUCAAAUUAUGGAGUGGAAAAAGCGUAAUGUUAAUAUCUUGUAAAUUCGUAUUCCCUAUUAAAUAAAGCUUUCUUAUUCCCUAAA